GAAAGGUCACAGCGCGGCAGCGGGUCUGGCUGGCGGCAGCGGCGGGAGGGAGCCGAGAGACCCGAGUGCACGUGUGGAGAAGCGGCGGCACAAGCGCGGCGGCGGGAGACACUCCCGCCCCCACCAGACUCAAGCCCUCACUCGACUCUCGCGGCCUUCGUUGCUCGCACAGCUCCCUGCCCAGGCUAGGAGGCCGGCUUGCGGGGUUGAGUGGCCCGAGCUAAGGGUGCGGAGACCUAAGGGCGGCGACUACGACGGCGUUGAUAUCGGUGGUAACGACGGCCUCAGCAGGCGGGGAAGAUGAAAGGUAGCCGGAUCGAGCUGGGAGAUGUGACACCACACAAUAUUAAACAGUUGAAAAGAUUGAAUCAGGUCAUCUUUCCAGUCAGCUACAAUGACAAGUUCUACAAGGAUGUGCUGGAGGUUGGCGAGCUAGCAAAACUUGCCUAUUUCAAUGAUAUUGCUGUAGGUGCAGUAUGCUGUAGGGUGGAUCAUUCACAGAAUCAGAAGAGACUUUACAUCAUGACACUAGGAUGUCUGGCACCUUACCGAAGGCUAGGAAUAGGAACUAAAAUGUUAAAUCAUGUCUUAAACAUCUGUGAAAAAGAUGGUACUUUUGACAACAUUUAUCUGCAUGUCCAGAUCAGCAAUGAGUCGGCAAUUGACUUCUACAGGAAGUUUGGCUUUGAGAUUAUUGAGACAAAGAAGAACUACUAUAAGAGGAUAGAGCCCGCAGAUGCUCAUGUGCUGCAGAAAAACCUCAAAGUUCCUUCUGGUCAGAAUGCAGAUGUGCAAAAGACAGACAACUGAACAAAUUACAAAUGAACUUUCUUGCACUUGCUUGUCGCCAAAUAAAAGAGAGGCCCAUUGAUUCCUCCCCCACCCCAACACUUUUCUUUUAAAGCUUUUCUCCCUCCUUGUUCUUGUUUUUCUUUCUUCCUUUCCUUUUCUCUGAGAGUUUUAAUACUUUCAAGGACUUUAAAAAAAUAAUCAUGUUUGAAUUGUUUUCUCUUAUUUUUGUGAGGUGGUUUGAAGGAAGGACAAGGUAGAUCUGUUUAGUUUUGCAGUUGAAGUUAGAUGGUCCUAAACAUUUAAUUGUCAAAUAAUUUCAAAUUUAAUGUCCUGCUUUCACAUUGAAGGGCAGAGCCUACAAAACAUUGUAUAUUUCAAAAGACAAAAAGAAGCAGCAGCAGUAUCUUGUUCUCUAAUUCAUAGACAAGUUGAGUGUGUUUGUGGUACUUUGGGUUUUUAAACACUUUGGGAUACUAAUCCCUAGACAUUGCCUUCACUCCACCUUUAGUCCUUCUGAGCACUCUCUCGGGAGUUGGAACAUUGUUAUCCUUGUAAGAAAUACUAAGCUUAUGUUGAUUUUUAAGUAAUUAUAUCUUCUCUUCUUGCUGGUGGGUGGGGCAGUUUGGUUUAGUGUUAUACUUUGGUCUAAGUAUUUGAGUUAAACUGCUUUUUUGCUAAUGAGUGGGCUGGUUGUUAGCAGGUUUGUUUUUCCUGCUGUUGAUUGUUACUAGUGGCAUUAACUUUUAGAAUUUGGGCUGGUGAGAUUAAUUUUUUUUAAUAUCCCAGCUAGAGAUAUGGCCUUUAACUGACCUAAAGAGGUGUGUUGUGAUUUAAUUUUUUCCCGUUCCUUUUUCUUCAGUAAACCCAACAAUAGUCUAACCUUAAAAAUUGAGUUGAUGUCCUUAUAGGUCACUACCCCUAAAUAAACCUGAAGCAGGUGUUUUCUCUUGGACAUACUAAAAAAUACCUAAAAGGAAGCUUAGAUGGGCUGUGACACAAAAAAUUCAAUUACUGUCAUCUAAUGCCAGCUGUUAAAAGUGUGGCCACUGAGCAUUUGAUUUUAUAGGAAAAAAUAGUAUUUUUGAGAAUAACAUAGCUGUGCUAUUGCACAUCUGUUGGAGGACAUCCCAGAUUUGCUUAUACUCAGUGCCUGUGAUAUUGAGUUUAAGGAUUUGAGGCAGGGGUAAUUAUUAAACAUAUUGCUUCUAUUCUUGGAAAAAUAGAAGUGUAAAAUGUUAAUAAUACAAAUGUCACUGUGACCUCCUCCACUGAGAGGACUGGUUUAUGCCAGAUCAUUUUCCGGCACACACGGAGUGGCUUUGACAGAUUGAUAACUUUGUAAGAUGGGAGACAUCUGAAAUAUUCAUGUUUUCCUUUUGUAGUCCCAUCUCCACUAUUUAGAAAUGUUCUCAGACUUUAAAAUAAUGCACAGGGCUUGAGCUUUCUGUCAUUUGACUUUAAAAGGAAGUUUCAUUCAUAUUUAUCCUCUUAUGUAAAAUUGCGGUAUAAAGUCUCAUUUCCAAAUAUGUUAAAUGACAAAAUUAUUUUAUAAAAUGUUUAUGCACACUUUAUAACCUUAAGUUUUUAUUUGAGAAUGUGAAAGUACAAAGUGCAGUAGACUUCAACAAUCUUGAGUGCCAAGAAUAAUACAGAAAAAGAAGACAGUUGAUGAAUGAGUUUAUAGGGUUCUAAUCUUAAGAUGGUAAAAAUGUAGAAAGACCUUGCUGGUUUUUUGGGGGUAUUCGUUUCUUAAACAAUCCAAAUCUAAGCUUAGAAGAAAAGUUUAGCGUUAAGCACCUUUAUCUUCAUGAAUAAGCUUCAGCUUGCUCUUGGCAAGAGAAGAGUGCUUGAGUUACAGAAGGCAUAAGUAGUUUGAAGAAUGCAGCAGCCUUUUUGUAAACUUCCCAGAUAUCAAAAUAGACUUUGAUAUAUAAAUGGUUUUCUGAGAUGACACUGCCUCUAUUUCUAUAACCAUUUCACCUGGACUAUCUAAUCAGUCCUAUGAAUGUAUCCCUAAAUGUGGUUAUUGAAAACCUAAUAGCUGCCUCAUGACAAGUACAUGUUAUUUAAGGAGGAAAAAAUAUUAAAUUUUGAAUUGAGUGUGUAGGCUCCCUAUCAUUAUAUAUAGAGUUUCUUUUUCCACGGUAGUCAGUGACUUAACCUGAAUUGUAAAUGUUUGUAAAGGGUUAAUUGUCCUACAUCAAACUUAGUUAAAUAAUUCCAUCCACUUAUGGAGGAGGAGGAGAAUGUGGAAGAGGUAAAAAGCUGGGCACAAGUUCAUAUGCCUAUGAGUCAGUAAAGACUGAAGUAAUGUCCUAUGUUGAGCUGGUUAUUUUGAUAUAUGAUAAUAAUUAUCUUUGAAGUAGAACAAUUCUGUUAACUGGAAAAUCACAGGAUAUAUCCAUCAUAUUUUUCAGGACAGAUAGUUUUUACUGUGGGGCAAAUAGGUUAAAAUUACACUAUGUUAGUUGCAUUUAGGUUUUAAAGCAAAGAAUCUGUAGAGAAAUCUAUGCAAUAUAUAGUUUGUCCAGAUUAGCUUUCAUUUGGGGAAUGAAGUUCUGAAAUAUCUAAAGCAGUUUACUCAUCAAUUGAAAAGUCCUCCAAAAAGAGAACUAUUGGGAAACCAUGGUGUGGUGGUGGAAAAGAAAAGCUCCCUCAGUUUUUUGGAGGGAAUAACUUAAAAAAAUACUUAAAUGGCUAAGUUUACUUGGUGCAGUUAAGAAUUAAACUUGUCAAUUUUAACAUUGCUGUUACAUCUGAAAUAAACUUAUGUGAUGUUCUGGUAGUGAUCUGUGAUAUCUGUAAAUGUCAAAACUGUAUUGUUGAAUUCUGCAGCCAGCAACCGUACAUACUCAUUGUGUAGUGUUUCCCUUACUGCUUUUAUUUACUUUCACAUUUAAGAUCUAAUUUUAAAAUCAUUAAAAUAGGCCAAGUGUAAUUAAGGCAUCCUAAUUCAGAUCUUCUGUGACUUGCUAGGUACAGUGCCCAAUAUCUACAAUUCAGUUCCAAUGAGAGGGAAAAAGUAAGAUCCAAGGAACUGUCUUGCUGCUGUAUUUUUAAUGUAAUUAUUAGAAAUACUUGACACUUUAGGCUGCAAUCUAGUUAGUAAUGUUUAUUGGCUACAGACAACAUAUUCAGGUGUUUUGUUUUUCUUCCUUGUAAGGAAGGAGUACGGUAGUUCAAUGAGUUGGGAAUUGGCUUUUAAGCUUUUUAUCAAACAUGAAUUUAAGAUUUUUUCUUUAACAGAAUUCAGUAUUUAAUAUUUCUAGUCAAAAUUGUUAUAAUUAGAUUUUUGCUUUUUUCAUUUAAGAAGCAAUGAGUGAUCCUUGUCUAGUGUGUCUCAGUUAUUACUGUAGUUUAAAACAACAAACAAGUAUUACCUUCCACAGUUCUGGAUCAGGAAUCUAGGAGCUGCUUAACUGGGUGGUUCUGUCUUGAGAUCUCAGAAGGUUGCAGUCAAGCUGUUAGCCAGGACUGUACCAUCUUGAAGCUUGACAAGGCUAGAGGAGCCAUUUCCAAGAUGUCUUGCUUACGUGGCUCUUGGGCUUCUGUUCCUCACUGUGUGGGUAUCACACACAGUGCCUGAUGCUCACGUGGCUCUUGGGCUUCAGUUCCUUGGGCACCAGUUGCCUGGUGGACAACUGGUAUGUGGCUUCCCCUAGAGCAGGUGAUAUAAGAAAGUGAGCAGAAACCAUACUUUUUUAUGACGUAGCCUCAGGUGACAUUAUUUCUGCCAUAUUCCAUGAGUCACACAGACCAACCAUUGAAUCAGCUUGGUAUAGUGUGGGAGGGGACUGCACAAGGAUGUGAAUACUGGGAGGUGGAUAUCAUUGGGCCCUCUAGGAGACUGGCUAUCACUGCUCAGAGAAGAUGCUGGGCUUCGUUGACUCCCAAGGUCAGGGUAGUUUUGGUUAGGUUGUGUUUUAUUAGUCUCUAAAAGGAGUAGUUUUCUAAAUGAGGGUUAUAAAGCACUGCACUUUACAGUUAUUCGGGAUAUAAAAGAAAUAGUGGGUCUAAAGGCUGUGCUCUUGUGGUUGGGUUUUCAGUGGGGAGGGGAGACUAGUCUGUCUCAGACUGAUGCUGUUCUCACUGAUUUGAAUAUUUCUGGGAAAUUGGAUACUACAGUCACAAAUAGGAACAGUAAGCCUAUAGAAGUUUUUCAGGGAGUAAAUAUUUUCUAUGGCAGUGUCCUGAAUUGGUUCUCCCUUGCAAGACUGAACUGUAGGAACUUAGUCCUAGUUUAUGAUACAGCCAAGUAACAUAGUCACAUGGGAAAAAGAGCUUGAGUCAGAUUUCUUAAUGUGUGUUGUUAACUUGGUAGAACAUUGAGAAUUAUUUAAGUCAGAGAACGAUCUGUUACUGGGGCAGAAAUUCUCAACCUUUUCAGUUCUCCAAAAUUUAAGAUACUUGAUUUCUUAGGUAAAAUGUUUUUGUUUUUGUUUUGGAGACAGAGUCUCGCUCUGUCGCCCAGGCUGGAGUGCAGUGGCGCGAUCUUGGCUCACUGCAAACUCCGCCUCCCAGAUUCAAGCAAUUCUGCCUGAGCCUCCCAAGUAGCUGCGACUAGAAAGCGCAUGCCACCACGCCUGGCUAAUUUUUUGUAUUUUAGUAGAGAUGGGGGUUUCACCGUGUUGCCCAGGCUGGUCUCAAACUCCUGAGCUUAGGCAAUCCUCCUGGGGCAGCCUCCCAAAGUGCUAGGAUUACAGGCGAGCCAUGGCGCCUGGCCAGUAAAAUGUUUUCUAUCUAGAAUGAAUCAAGGUAUUUUCCUUGCUCAGUAGCUUCUAGAAUAAGAAAAAAAUAGCAGCAAGAUCUGAUUCAGAAAUAGUUGGGAGCAGAAAGUUAAUAUGAAGGAGUUGCUACUUGUUAACAGCCUAGAGUUGAGAUCUAGAAGAAUUAUUACCUUUUUAAAUUUGUGAUGAAAGCUUAAAUCCAGCAUUUGGGAAGUUACUCUAUUGGCUGAACUAUUUUGGAGUUUGUAAGCUUUGUAUUAGAUAUUCCUGAUUUAACUGAAACUAAUUUGCCACAUAGCUUUAAUUUCAUCCCAGUUUUACUUGUUUUACUGUCCUCAAAAACUCAAGACAUCUGAACUCAAAGGAUCUAAGCAGUAUAAAUUAAAGCACAUGUUGAAUCACUGUAGCUUUCGUAGGACAUCUGAUUAUAAUGCUUUUCUUUGUUUCUUUGUCCAUACUGAACUUGUCUAGUUUAUCUUUGAGAAACAUUUGCUAGUAUCAAAAAUCUUCUGUAAAGAUUUGAACAAUCUUGAAUUCUCCUUGUCACUAGCCAUCUCUUCCCCUAAAGUAUAAUAAAACUGUCAGGUACUAUA